GGAGGGCACGUCGGCGCCUCGGCGAGGAUGGGAGUCCCCAGGACCCGGAGCUGAGCAGCCUGGCGCGCGGCGGGCAGGGCGCGCAGGACAGAAGCCUCGCUGUUCCUCCGGGAGCCCAACACCGUUCCCGCGCGGCCACGAUGAUCCCUCCGAGCAGCCCCCGCGAGGACGGCGUGGACGGGCUGCCCAAGGAGGCGGUGGGCGCCGAGCAACCGCCCUCUCCUGCAUCCACCAGCAGCCAGGAAUCCAAGCCCUAUGGAUGACGUGAACUGAGUGGUUCUUGACCCAGAAAACCAAAUGAACUCUUGAGGAAUCAUGUCCAUCAAAAGUUUAGUUGGCCUGUAGUGCUGAGAGCAACACAAAUGAUUCUGCACAGUGACACUGACUUGAAGAUAUCUUGUAUCCACUCCAUCCAUCCACGUGCAUCUUGGGGAAAAAUAGAGGAGGCAAGUCAUGCAUUAAAUUAUCAAGGUAAUAUAUUUCAGCUCCAGAAACUAAAACGAUCACUUUCUUUCAAGACCAAGAGUUUACGGAGCAAAAGUGCUGACAACUUCUUCCAGCGAACCAACAGCGAAGACAUGAAACUGCAAGCACACAUGGUGGCUGAGAUCAGCCCCAGCUCCAGCCCACUCCCUGCUCCAGGAAGCCUGACGUCCACACCCGCCAGGGCUGGUCUGCAUCCAGGUGGCAAGGCUCAUGCCUUUCAGGAAUACAUCUUCAAGAAGCCCACUUUCUGUGAUGUCUGCAACCACAUGAUAGUGGGAACAAAUGCUAAGCAUGGACUGCGCUGCAAAGCCUGUAAGAUGAGCAUCCACCACAAGUGCACAGAUGGCCUGGCACCCCAGCGGUGCAUGGGCAAGCUGCCAAAGGGGUUUCGGCGUUACUACAGCUCCCCCUUGCUCAUUCAUGAACAGUUUGGCUGCAUUAAAGAAGUUAUGCCCAUUGCCUGUGGCAAUAAGGUGGACCCUGUCUACGAGACCCUCCGCUUCGGCACCUCCCUGGCCCAGAGGACAAAGAAGGGCAGCUCCGGCAGUGGCUCUGACUCACCUCACAGAACCUCUACUUCAGAUCUUGUGGAGGUUCCUGAGGAAGCCAAUGGGCCAGGAGGCGGGUAUGACCUAAGGAAACGCAGCAACAGCGUGUUUACAUAUCCAGAAAAUGGCACUGAUGAUUUCAGAGAUCCAGCGAAGAACAUAAACCACCAGGGAUCUCUUUCCAAAGACCCAUUACAGAUGAACACCUAUGUUGCCUUGUACAAAUUUGUACCACAGGAGAAUGAAGAUUUGGAAAUGAGGCCAGGAGACAUAAUUACUCUUUUAGAGGAUUCCAAUGAAGACUGGUGGAAAGGGAAAAUUCAAGACAGAAUUGGCUUCUUUCCAGCCAACUUUGUUCAGAGACUACAACAAAAUGAGAAGAUUUUUAGAUGUGUUAGAACCUUCAUUGGGUGUAAGGAACAGGGGCAGAUAACACUGAAAGAGAAUCAGAUCUGCGUGAGUUCUGAAGAAGAACAAGAUGGUUUUAUCAGAGUCCUCAGUGGAAAAAAGAAAGGCCUCAUCCCCCUUGAUGUACUAGAAAACAUCUGAUUGCUGGCUCCUCCUCCGUUUGCAGUAGGCAAGCUCUGCUGCGAUGCCUCUGCCUCAUCUCACACUGCGUCAACCCAAAGGAGCUGCCGCACUGACCCAGCCCCCCAGGAAACAGUGAGACAAGAAUCAAGUAUCUGAGACUGUGGAGUAAUAGCCACAAAACAGAGGGCCCACUGCACAGCAUAUCCAGGCUGCCACAGGUGGGGACGAGGCUGAGAGAGUCAGCAGGCAGAGCCAGAUGCCAUGCUUGGCAGCAGCAGUAGGACUAUAAACCACAGCUGUCCCCCAGGAUCCCACUCCUUUCCUGUCUGUGUGGUGUAAGUUAACACACUGGAGUGUGCUCCAGUUUGCAGGGUAGCCCAGUGCAAGGUUCAGAUCCAUGUAGCUAAGUAUUAUCCUGCUUCCAGACCUAUGUCACCAGUACCAAUCAGUCAGUGUCAUCACAUUUCAGGCCCCAAGCAAUCUCUGUGCAAAGCAUCAGAAAGACCUGCUUCCCAGCCCCCAGCAUUCCAGUGCUCUCCAGGCUUCCUCUCUUUGUGAUUGUGCUGUCCAGAGUGUCCAGCUUGUUCUUUCUUUCUCUUCAGUCCUCUGAGUACAUCUGGUGGUGUGCAUUAGAUGUGAGGGCUAUGUUGACAUGGCAUCACCUCCAAAGACCUGACCUGCCUAAAGACUGAUGACAGGCCAUCCUUCCUGCUGUUCUAGGUACUGGCCUGGGUGACAGAGCAGGACAUGAGACAUAGAUACAGUGGGGAGGAGAAGUGGGGAAAGGUGGAGCAGAGAGUUCUUACUUAUUGAAGAUUAUACAGCCCUUUCGGUUAUGAAGUCCCUGCUUGAAGGCAAUGGACCUGGGGAAGAGACUAUCACAAAAAGUCUCCAUUUUCAUUUUACAUCCUCUCUAUUGGAGGCAGCACUUUUCCCUCAUGCUGUCCUAUAGGACUCCACUUUGAAGGUUGUGCCUACGUUGCAGGGAACUAGGAACAUGGAGGGGAACCAACAACAGCAUCUUAGAAGAAAUGUAGCCAAAUUGGAGUCCAUUCUUCUUUAGGGCAGUAUAUGAAAUCCUAGCAGAUGUAAAAUGGAAAAGAAUCCUAAUGCUUCUUCCUUCAGAAAGUAGAGGAACUAGGGGCCCAAUUAGCAUCAUCUAGGGGAAUCUCUAUUACUCUGUACUUAUACUAAUGUUUACAAGAAUGCAAUAUACUGUGAUGCCUUCCUACUCAAGCCUCCUAGCAUUCAAACUUCCAUCCUAUUAGUCAUUAACAUGGUUAAACUUCAAUUCACAAUCACCUUGGAAUCAAUGUCAGUUUGAUUUAUUUUGUUACAGAGCAAUAAAAUCAUUAGAACAAUGGUUUUUAAAAGACUUAAGUGGAUGCAUCCUAUGCAUGUAAGCAUUAUUUCCCAAACCAAAGCAUCAUUCAUCUCCAUUUAUUUCUUUUGUUCCCGCUCAGUGUGAAGUUGGGAACUGAGAGGGGAUGGCUGCUGGUUUCACAGAAGUUUGGAUGCCUUACUCUUAUCUUAAAGCCAGCAUCCAGAAUUUCCUCCCUCUCUGAUGCCACAUGCAAAACCAGGUGUACGAUGUCAAGAUGGAUUCUUUGAGAGCCAGGGUAGAUCAUAUGACUGCCUUUCUGUAAAAUUGGAUGCCUAGUACAAAUGCUCUUUGCCUCUAAUUCAGUAUUCCAUUUAAUAAAAACAAUACAGUGGCUGGAAAGGAGCAUCAGAAA